CUUACCCGCACUUUACAGGUGAACACAUCGAAAGUUCAGAGAUCCGCCUGAAAUCAGCCAGCCAGUAUGUGGCCAAAUGAGGGUUUGAAACCAGGACUGUCUUAUUUCAAAACUUGUGCUCUUUCUAAUACAUGCUACUGUUUCCUGAUGAGAUUGCCACAUUGCACAAUGUGGCACCAAGGGGCACCAUUCACAUGGUCAUCAGUAUAAAUGGCACCUGGGAAUUGAACAGCAUAGUGGCUAGGUAUCCUAAGAUCAGAGGCACGAUCUCCAUUAAAUAGCAGCUAUUGCAGAGGAGAAAUGACGAGGACCUAACCUGGAGGGGUUGGAAAGGAAGGGACAACUUCGAGAGACAUUUAAGAGAUAGAUUUGACAGAAUUGGCAGUUGACUGGGUGUGGAGUUAAGAAAUAAGGGAGUUGAGGCUGUCUCUGAAGUUUCUAGCUUAGGUGCCUGGGAGAAUAGUAAUGCCCUUAUUGGUUAGGAAGGCAAAGGGGAAGGGGCUGUUGGGCAGAAAACAUCACGGAAUGCCACUUCCCCUGCUUACCCAUUUGACCUGGGUUAGGAGAUGAACUUGAUUUAAGGGUACCACCUGGACCUGUGCUUUGGUUUCUUGCUUUUCUACUUAAGGUCAAACUCAGAAACAAUCUGGGCCAUUAAAAGUUCUUGUGCUUUUAGCUGUAGUUGACUAACCUGGUCCUGUCCUCAGGAUUGACUAAAUCCCACCCCCAGUGAUGGGACUUGCCUGCUUAGCCCAGCUGAACAUGUCCCCGGGGCCCUGCUUCCCCUAGACCUCCCUUGCAGAAGCUGCCCACAAGGUCUGCCCAACCUUUCCCUUAUCCCUCCAUGUUCCCAGACACCAGACACUAAAGCUCUACAUUUCUUGGCACUGGACCCUGUGUGGUAUAAGGCAUGGUCGGCCCCUUGCAGCCAUGGUAAUCUCACAGUUUCCCAGACCCUCUCUUCCUCUCAUCCUCCAACAAAACUACCUGAGCUCUAGGACCUCCACCUGUCUGGGGCCAUGCCCAACUCAGCCCCCACUCAGAGCCUGUCCUUGCUCCCUGGCCCAGGCGAUGAACAGGCUGUAGACCCAUAAAGCUUCCUGCAGCUUGCAGUGAAUGGAUGCCUGUUUGUAAACCAGGACAUUGGACAUGGCACGUCUGCUGCAGAAAGUGAGGGGCGCCCUUCCACGUAGCUCUCAAGCCAUUAUCCGUGAAGCAUUCCUUCAUCUCAGGGUAACAUCUGCCCGUAUCCACUUGUGGCUCUGACCUGACCUUCAACUAUAGCUAUUUGGACCCUUACAUACCAUUGUAUACACAAAGAUUUGCACACAUGUAUGCACACAUGCACACACACACACACACACACACACACACUUUUAAAAAUGUUUUUCAUGUGAAAGCCCAGUGAUGAUAAAGCAAGCUGUCAGGAUUUAAAAAAAAAAUACAAUAAUGCAAUUCACAGAGGACAGUCAGUGGUUAGCACAGCUUCUACUCAUGUUUUUACACCUUCUGGAGGUGUGACAGGGUGUGCUUGGUGUUAGAGUUGGCCACAGUGAGACCCCAAGGCAUUAAGAUGUCUUCAAUCAACUGUCCUCAAAACAGCGUUGACCAAACAGCUUUUAGGUACCAAGCACUCUCUAGAUGCAGUGUGAACUUCAAAAAUGAGGCAGACAUAUCUUUGCUUCCUGGAAACACACAGCCCCCUGUAGAGAGAGACCACAUGUGUGAACAAACAAUGCAACAUGGGGUCCAUCACAAAGCCACCCACACUUGGAGUAGUGGAAGACCUGGUCCUGGUCUCUGCCCCACCACUUGGCUUUACCAGGUCCCAUUUGCUCUGUUCUUCACCCUCAUUCCCUGGUUUGGGACAAUGGGAGUCGAUUCCUGUUGGGAGCAGGGACCCUCAGGAUAUCCCUUCCUGGGAUAUUUAUAAGAAGAGGAUCAAGGUCCCCAUGAGAACCUGUUCCACCCGAGGGACUGUUCCUUUCUGUCAUUGAGUUCUCACUCCAGAGAAUGGACAGCCUUGUGGAUGAUCGUGUCAACAUCCUGGGAUUUUCCAUUUUCAACCAAUCCCAUGCUUUCUUCCAAGAGUUUGCCCAGAGCCUCAACCAGUCCUGGCAGGAGAACUGUGACCAUGUGCCCUUCACUGGGCCUGCGCUCUCCUCGGCCCUGCUGUUUGAUGCUGUCUAUGCUGUGGUGACUGCGGUGCAGGAACUGAACCGGAGCCAAGAGAUCGGCGUGAAGCCCUUGUCCUGCGGCUCGGCCCAGAUCUGGCAGCACGGCACCAGCCUCAUGAACUACCUGCGCAUGGUAGAAUUGGAAGGUCUUACCGGCCACAUUGAAUUCAACAGCAAAGGCCAGAGGUCCAACUACGCUUUGAAAAUCUUACAGUUCACAAGGAAUGGUUUUCGGCAGAUCGGCCAGUGGCACGUGGCAGAGGGCCUCAGCAUGGACAGCCACCUCUAUGCCUCCAACAUCUCGGACACUCUCUUCAACACCACCCUGGUCGUCACCACCAUCCUGGAGAACCCAUAUUUAAUGCUGAAGGGGAACCACCAGGAGAUGGAAGGCAAUGACCGCUACGAGGGCUUCUGUGUGGACAUGCUCAAGGAGCUGGCAGAGAUCCUCCGAUUCAACUACAAGAUCCGCCUGGUUGGGGAUGGCGUGUACGGCGUUCCCGAGGCCAACGGCACCUGGACGGGAAUGGUCGGGGAGCUGAUCGCUAGGAAAGCAGAUCUGGCUGUGGCAGGCCUCACCAUUACAGCUGAACGGGAGAAGGUGAUUGAUUUCUCUAAGCCAUUCAUGACUCUGGGAAUUAGCAUUCUUUACCGCGUUCAUAUGGGACGCAAACCCGGCUAUUUCUCCUUCCUGGACCCAUUUUCUCCGGGCGUCUGGCUCUUCAUGCUUCUAGCCUAUCUGGCCGUCAGCUGUGUCCUCUUCCUGGUGGCUCGGUUGACGCCCUACGAGUGGUACAGCCCACACCCAUGUGCCCAGGGCCGGUGCAACCUCCUGGUGAACCAGUACUCCCUGGGCAACAGCCUCUGGUUUCCGGUCGGGGGGUUCAUGCAGCAAGGCUCCACCAUCGCCCCUCGCGCCUUAUCCACCCGCUGUGUCAGUGGCGUCUGGUGGGCAUUCACGCUGAUCAUCAUCUCAUCCUACACGGCCAACCUGGCAGCCUUCCUGACCGUGCAGCGCAUGGAUGUGCCCAUUGAGUCAGUGGAUGACCUGGCUGACCAGACCGCCAUUGAAUAUGGCACAAUUCACGGAGGCUCCAGCAUGACCUUCUUCCAAAAUUCCCGCUACCAGACCUACCAACGCAUGUGGAAUUACAUGUAUUCCAAGCAGCCCAGCGUGUUCGUGAAGAGCACAGAGGAGGGAAUCGCCAGGGUGUUGAAUUCCAACUACGCCUUCCUCCUGGAAUCCACCAUGAACGAGUACUAUCGGCAGCGAAACUGCAACCUCACUCAGAUUGGGGGCCUGCUGGACACCAAGGGCUAUGGGAUUGGCAUGCCAGUCGGCUCGGUUUUCCGGGACGAGUUUGAUCUGGCCAUUCUCCAGCUGCAGGAGAACAACCGCCUGGAGAUCCUGAAGCGCAAAUGGUGGGAAGGAGGGAAGUGCCCCAAGGAGGAAGAUCACAGAGCUAAAGGCCUGGGAAUGGAGAAUAUUGGUGGAAUCUUUGUGGUUCUUAUUUGUGGCUUAAUCGUGGCCAUUUUUAUGGCUAUGUUGGAGUUUUUAUGGACUCUCAGACACUCAGAAGCAACUGAGGUGUCCGUCUGCCAGGAGAUGGUGACCGAGCUGCGCAGCAUUAUCCUGUGUCAGGACAGUAUCCACCCCCGCCGGCGGCGCGCCGCAGUCCCGCCGCCCCGGCCCCCCAUCCCCGAGGAGCGCCGACCGCGGGGCACGGCGACGCUCAGCAACGGGAAGCUGUGCGGGGCAGGGGAGCCCGACCAGCUCGCGCAGAGACUGGCGCAGGAGGCCGCCCUGGUGGCCCGCGGCUGCACGCACAUCCGCGUCUGCCCCGAGUGCCGCCGCUUCCAGGGCCUGCGGGCACGGCCGUCGCCCGCCCGCAGCGAGGAGAGCCUGGAGUGGGAGAAAACCACCAACAGCAGCGAGCCCGAGUAGUCCCGGAGGCCACAGGACGCGCAGAGGCCGGGCGGGGCGGGAGGGGAGGGGCGGGGCGGGCGCUGCUGUCAGCCGCCAGCCGGAACUUGUACAGCGUCGACACCUCUCCAGAUUUCGGAUCCAGUCACUUUUCAAAAAGAUCAAGGAGCCUGACGCCCCAGCCAGAGACCGCGCCCGGUCAGGGAGCAGGGUCCACCCGGAAACGUUGCACCCAAAGGGCAAAGGACGGCCCUCCCUCCUGGGCACAAGGACCCAUCUUCUCCCAGUGGGUCUUUCCCUCUCGCCAAAAUAACAAGAGUAUAGGGUGGGGGGUCCCUACCCAGACCAGUCCAAUGAAUUGGUGGAAUCAUCAGUUGAAUUUCCCCCUAGUCAGGGGCCAAUGUACCCUCCGUCUAGUUCUUACAGAAAAAAAAAAAAUUAAACAGGGAAGUUUUUCUUUUCUGGAUUUGUAUAUUUUUGUUAAUGUUCUUUUCCCUUUUCUUUCCUCCUCUCCUUUUCUUCUUUGUCAUCUUCUCAGUCCUGUUAAUUUGUUUUGUGUUUUUUGGAGGGGGAGGCUGGGUUAGGGAAUGGAAGCCUAAAUAAUCCCUAUUUCUUCUUUUUCCUGAAUUUUGGAAUAUUGCGUUACCAGUGCAUCCGAUUUCAGGUGCUUAACUCUCUGUAUGGUGACUGAGGGGCCUGCAGGAGCACAGGAGAAGGAGUCUUGGGAAGAAUCAGAUGGAGAGUCUCAAAAGUCCAUUGCAGUAAACUUUGAGAUGCCAAAAAGCAAUUAACUCAUCCUAUACUCAGACCUUGAAACGCCUGGAAUGUCAAGGGUUAAUCUGUCUUUUCUUUCCCUUUCUCUUUCUGACUGUCACUAUUACUGGGUUUGAUUUGAUCUUUUUGUGAAUGUAGUCUCUGAAGACAGACAGGGGAGGAGAACAGAAUGCACAAAGUAUCCUAGGACUUUGUUUAAGGAGCGGAAAGAGCAGAUAGAAUUUUCCCAUACCAUGGCCUUGGCUUCCGGUGGAACGUGCCGUUCACAGAGGCGGAAGGACUGGGCCACCCCGUUGGUAUGGUGCAUACUUUGUCAACUGCAUCUCUUUUCAACCAAACUCAAAUGAGUGGCUGCCUAUGAAGCCAGACCCCCAAGACUAUCAUGGAUUGGGUGGUUUCUUGCUACUUAGACGUGAGACCUGGGUGCAAGUGUAUGUGUGUGUAUGUGUGCGCGCGUGUGCGUGUGUGUAUUUAUUCAACAGAAAGACCUUAAGUAUUCAAGAAUUUGCUAGGUUCCUGGGAGAGAGGUGGAGUCUCCUAGUCAAUACACGGGCCUGGGAACCAGGAACUCUUGAGUCGUAACCUCAGCUUGAGCAGUAGCCCUCCCACCUUGUAUGACUUUAGGUAAAGCAUUUAACUUCUCUUCCAUCUACCAAAUAGGAGUUACUGAUGCUGUCCAGGUUACCAGGUGACUGCUAGUGACUGCUCUCCAUGUGAGAAGUUUGCAGAGUCCAGAGCACACAUCUGAUGGGAGGGGCGAGGCUUUCUACAGCUGCUUGACCUUUGCUUGGCUUCACUAAUUGGGAGUUUCACGCAGAGUUCUCAUUGGCUGAUGGAAAACAAAUUCUAUGCAAUUUCUGAUUGUAAACUUAGAAAAUUCAGAGAGAAACAAACAGCCGCUACCAACCACCUCCACCUCCACCACCGCUGCCACCACCUUGAAUGGAAUUGUCCUCACUUUUGUUGCUGUUGCAAAUGUACUAAAAUAAAGACAUCUUUGGAAGAUGACGAGCUUAAUUCAUGUUUUUGCCAUUUGGGUUGGUCGGCAUCCUCUUUAUGCCAGGACAAUCAGUUAGGGCUGCCGUCCUGGGGGCCAAAUGGUACCCUGAUUAUUCCUGUGAGGGAUACUCGUUUUGUCCUCACCUGACCUCACUCAUGAAUUUGAAUCCUUUAUCUUUUUUCUCUUUAACCAUCAAAUGACAACAAGCUGUGCAAGACACUUGUGUCUUUUUUUAAACCUUGCCUUGAUCCUCGUGGAGAAACGUGGAUUUGGUGGGAAGGGCACCCGAAGGCCAGCUGACAACAAACCCCAAUGGUGCCACUCUGCUCCAACCUGCAGCUCCAUCCUAUGCUUCUCACAGACAACGUGGUUCCUACUGUCAGAUCACAUUUGGGGCGGGAAGGGUGGUUUUUUAAAAAAACUCGUUUUUAUGAGCAGGCUAUCUUGAUCAAUAGCAAACUUUUUUUAAUGGAUUAGUGAAAUAAAUGUCCCCAUGCAUCAUUUAUAGUCUGUUUCUUUCUCCGUGUGGAAUCAAGAUAAGACUGCCAGCACUAGACGGUUUCUGUUAGCUGCUGAGACCAGGGCCUCACCUUGCUCAAGCUAGUGGGUGAAUUUGCAACCAGCUAAUACUCUUCCUUGGUUUGUUUCCACUUUUUAUCUGUUGGUUGUUGGCUUUCUUUUCCAUUCUGUAUUUUCUAUCUGACUCUGUAUACUGUAUAAAGCAGUUUUUUCUUGUCUGUUUAUCUUUCUUCAACUGGAAUAUUUACAAUAAAACAGAAACAAAUCCUGAAAUGUUAGUGAUGGAUGACAGCUGUUUGGGUUUAGAAAGUAUGGUUCAGUGUGUCUAAUAUCCAGGUACUAGACUUGAAAAGCAAAUAAAAUCAUAAACCCAC